CCAGCCCAGUGGCCCAUUCACGCGGCCGCCAGGGCUUCAUUCACCCCUGGCCGGGAGGGCAGCGCCCCCGUGACUCGCAGCUGGGGCUUCUCCACGGGUGGCGGCUGCAUCGCUCUGCCAGUGACGCUGGGCUGGUCCCUGGGGGCCCUCCUGCUGCUGUGGGGGUGCAGGGGUGGAUGCUGGCCCCAGGAUGCUGCACACGGCCUCAGGGCAGCACCCACACACUGGCAGCUCCAGCUUCCCCUGAAAGAUGACCGAGGAGGUGGGGAGGACGCGGUGCUGGCCAGCAGUGACGGCUGCAGCAUGUGUGGGCAGGUGCCGUGCCACACCUUUUACAAACAUCUGAAUGCAGCCCUCCCAACAGCCCGGGGGAAGGAAGUGUGGUCACAUGGCAGCCUUCCUGGGAUGUGACCCCAGCUCCAGGUGGCACAGCUCCCUUCUCCUGUGGCCUUGGAGCCCUGAGGGGACCCUACUUGAUGUCUCUGGGGUCUCCUGGCUGCUUCAUUUGCCCUCAAGACGGCUGUGGGGGCAGGGUCGCUGGGACCUUGGGGCAGAGGAGGGACUGAUCAAGUGCCUGCUGGGUGGCAGAGCAGCCACAUCCCCCCAUCCCCCCAAGCAAGCCCGGAAGGCAGGGGCUGGCGUCUUCUUCCUGUCCUCGGCCGAGGGGGAGCAGAUCAGCUUCCUGUUCGACUGCAUCGUCCGAGGCAUCUCCCCCACCAAGGGCCCCUUUGGGCUGCGGCCGGUUCUACCAGACCCAAGUCCCCCGGGACCCUCGACUGUGGAGGAGCGUGUGGCCCAGGAAGCCCUGGAAACCCUACAGCUGGAGAAGCGGCUGAGCCUCCUCUCACAUGCGGGCAGGCCGGGCAGUGGAGGGGAUGACCGCAGCCUGUCCAGCUCAUCCUCAGAGGCCAGUCACUUGGACGUCAGCGCCAGCAGCCGGCUCACCGCAUGGCCAGAGCAAUCCUCGUCGUCAGCCAGCACGUCACAGGAGGGGCCUAGACCAGCAGCUGCCCAGGCCGCCGGGGAAGCCAUGGUGGGUGCCUCAAGGCCACCCCCCAAGCCGCUGCGUCCGCGGCAGCUGCAGGAGGUUGGCCGCCAGAGCUCCUCGGACAGCGGCAUCGCCACUGGCAGCCACUCCUCUUACUCCAGCAGCCUCUCGUCCUACGCGGGCAGCAGCCUGGACGUGUGGCGGGCCACAGAUGAACUGGGCUCACUGCUCAGCCUGCCAGCAGCGGGGGCCCCCGAGCCCAGCCUGUGCACCUGCCUGCCCGGGACAGUCGAGUACCAGGUGCCCACCUCCCUGCGGGCCCACUAUGACACACCACGCAGCCUUUGCCUGGCUCCUAGAGACCACAGCCCCCCCUCACAGGGCAGCCCCGGCAACAGUGCGGCCAGGGACUCAGGCGGCCAGACGUCCGCCGGGUGUCCCUCUGGCUGGCUGGGCACGAGACGGCGGGGCCUGGUGAUGGAGGCCCCCCAGGGCAGCGAGGCCACACUGCCUGGCCCUGCCCCUGGCGAGCCCUGGGAAGCAGGCGGCCCCCACGCGGGGCCACCCCCGGCUUUCUUUUCGGCAUGUCCAGUCUGUGGAGGACUCAAGGUAAACCCCCCUCCUUGAGAGCCGCAGAUCCCGCCCCGCGGCUGCAAAGGGGCUGAAUUUGCCCCCAGAUGGCAGAGGAAGUGGCGCCAGCCUCCUUGCAGACUGGUGCUCUGUGUUCUGUGGGAGGGACCGGGGGUCUCCCGGAGAGGGGAGCUGGAGGGCGCGCCCUGUGGCUGCCACCGGAGGAAGGGGCUGACUUGGGGAGGUGAGUUCUGGAAGGCAGGGGCUCUGGGUCCGGCAGGUCGGGGUCACCAGAGCCCCAAUGCUCAGCUGCUUCACUCCGUGUCCCCCACCCCUGAGGAUCAGGUGAGUGCUGCACCUCUGUUGGCUCGUGCCUUGCACUGGGGUGCCAAGGGCUGGAGGCCCUGCCGCUGGCCUUGUCCUCCUUGGGCCUCACGCCCCCUUCGGGGGUGGCCGGUUCUCCCCAUCACCUCUCUGGGGCAGUCACACCACCUGUUAAGCAUCAAGCUACCACAGAGGCUCCGGCCACCUGGGCUCCACCAGCCCAGCCCCCCUGGGCUCCGUGUGCGCUGGGCCUCAUCCCCAUCUAUGGGAGGAAACUGAAGCUCAGGAGGCUGUGUGGCUUGCGGGGUCUCUGGGUUCUGGGCCCCACUGUUCCCCAGUGAAGCCCUUGUGGGAAGGUUCCGGGAGCAGGUGGUGUCCUCAGAGCAGCCUCGCCUGCUGACCCCACUGGGAGAGGCGCCGUGCCUCGGGCCCCUGGUGGGAGCUCUGCUGGCUCCUGUCUGAACCUCCUCGCAGGGCCAAAGGCUGGCUUGGCCUGUGUUUCCCCUGGCCCAGGCCUCAGCCCCUGCGUCGGAGGUGGGGCUGUGUUGGGCCCAUUGUCCCCCGCCCUGGGUGGCUUCCUCUUGCACAGCCUGGAGCCUGCCCUGACCACAGCCCAGCAGCUCCCUGUGAACACCUCUUUGUCCCUUCACUGUCAGCUGUUUCUAAACCCAGACACUGUUUGUAAUAGACUGGAAAUAAAAUGUUCUUUCCUUA